GUGUCUGGGGGCCGCGCCCAGCUGGGUCGGGACGCGCUCCCUGAGCUGCCCGAGCUCCGCGGGGACUCGGGCCGGGAUCCUCGGGCGGCUGCAUUGGCCGGGGCCGGGGCCGGGAGCGGGCCAUGAUGGGCCGGCGGCGCGCCUUCGCCGUGGACGGCCGGGAUGGGGCUGGCGAGGGCCUGGCACGGGGCUGCAUAGUGCCUGGAGUCACCAGCACCUACAGACGGAUCCCCGACGCUGCCCACGGGUGCUCAUCCUGGGAGAGAGGUGACAAGUUCAGAGGUGUCGGCAGGGAGGCACUCUUUCUCAAACUGGCCUCCCGGGACUCAGGAGUGGAGAUGGCAGUUGGGGACAGCCCCCUGGCCGCCUUACCGGGCCUUUCUCAGGACUCCCUGGACUUUGAAUCCUCAGGGAGUUCUGAGCCCCCCGCCCAGGUAGGCCGACUCCUGGCCAGCCAGAAGCUGGGGGAGGUGUUGGAGCGGUCCCGCCGGCUCCCAACAGCUCCCACCAGCUUGUCAGGACAACACCGCUCCCUGCGGCUGGCAAGCAAGCCUGAGCGUGAAGUGCCCCUUGGAGCAGGGCAACAGGAGUCCAUGGAGGCAGACACAGACCUAGAGGCAGGCCUGGAAGAAGAGGCGGUGGGGGGCCUGGGGCCUGGAGCCUGGGCCUGCCUCCCCGGGCAGGGUCUUCGCUAUCUGGAACACCUGUGCCUGGUGCUGGAGCAGAUGGCAAGGCUCCAGCAGCUCUACCUGCAGCUGCGGAUCCAGAGGCCCCCAGGGGAUCCCGGCGAGGAGGAGUCGACCCGAGCCCCUUUACCGUCCCCGUUACACACCCCAGGCAAUCGGGGGCAGGGGCCAUGGGAGCUGCUAAGCCAGACAGAGCACACAGGAGCAAAGGCUGCUUCACCCCCAAAGGUGGAGGUGCCCAGUGCCAACCCUCCCAGGCUGCCAGAAACCCCAGUGGAGCCAACGUACCACUUGCCAUCCUCCCAGGGACACAAGCGGGAUAUCUCCCACUGGGACAAGGUCAAGGUCCUGCUCAACCGGAUCUGCCGGAGAAGCCACCACCACCCUGAGCCCCCUGCCCCUCCUGAUGGCUCUGACCCCAGGAUCGAGUCCAGGGACCUCCCUGAAAGGCCUCAGUGCCGCCCCCACCGGAAGACCUUUAUGCCAUCAUUAGUGGUUAAGAAGCAACGAGCAAAAAACCUUUCUGUAGGCUGAGACCUCUCGGUGCACCUGGUGACCCUGGGUGGAGGGGACUUGCUGUGAAGUCUUCCUCGCCCUCUGCCCUCUUGCUGCUUCUCCACAUUGCCAGGAAAAGCUGCUGACGCCUGCCCUCCUCUCUUGAGUCGAGGGCUGAAUCUUUCUCCUCUAAGCAGUCUGGUCAGGAACCUUGGUUUCUUGAGAGGCCCCCAAGAUGCCGCAGCUCCAGGGCUCUUCCUCCUCACCAGAAAUCCCUGGGCUUCCACAAUGUGAACUCACUCAUUGUCAGGUGUCCGUGGAGUGUUUUUGGCAUGGUGACCUGUCUGGGCCCAGCAUGUUGCAGAUGUGUAUUUAUGCGCAAUGGUAUGCAUAUCUCUGUGUGACUGUCAGUGUUGCAAGCUGGCUGGAUCCAACCAUCUCUUCUGAAAUAAUGCAUCCAAAGGGUUGAUAUUCUGGGGGAGGUCACUGCAGAAGGAUGGAACUGACCUUUAUUCCCCAGUGGGCAGUUACUGAGCUUUCCUCCUCAGAGCCAUGCUGGCAGCCCUGGGACAGAGAACGGUGUGGCUUUGGCUGCCUCUGCAUGGAAUCUUGCCCCGGACUCCUGAAGACUGCACAAGGAAUGAGGAAGAUCAGGGACAACCUGGGAACUGAAUAACUUUCAAAGCCAGUGCUCAGCUUCUCUGCUCCGUACUAGCGUUUACAGGUCUUAAUUCAAACCAGAUGCCUGUACUAGUUUUUAGACCCCAAGUCAACCUUUCUGAGCCACAGCUUCCCGCUGGGAAUAAUGAUGCCUGCCCUAUCUACCUCACAGACUUGUUAUGAGGAUAAAGUGAGAUUAAACUGCCUCAAAGUGC